ACUAAUAAUACAAAACUCAGCCGGGCGUCCUGGCGCAUGCCUGUGAUCCCAGCUAUUUGGGAGGCUGAGGCAGGAGAAUCACUUGAACCCGGGAGGCGGAGGUUGCAGUGAGCCGAGAUUGCGUCACUCUACUCCAGCCUGGGCGACAGAGCGCAACUCUGUCUCUGGAAUGAAUGAAAGAAAGAAAGAAUGAAUGAAAGAAAGAAAGAAUGAAUGAAAGAAAGAAAGAAAGAAAAAGAAAGAAAGAGCGAGACUCUGUCUCUGGAAUGAAUGAAAGAAAGAAUGAAUGAAAGAAAGAAAAAAGAAAGAAAGAAAGGAAAGAAAAAGAAAGAAAGAAAGAAAUGGACUGUGCGUGGGCCAAGGAGACACAAGGGGAGAUGGGUCACUGCCCAAGCCGUCCCUCAGUGCCUGGCCCAGCUCGGUGGUCCCUGCCAACAGCAAUGUGACGCUGCGAUGUUGGACUCCUGCCAGAGGUGUGAGCUUUGUUCUCAGGAAGGGAGGAAUUAUUCUGGAGUCCCCGAAGCCCCUUGAUUCUACAGAGGGCGCGGCCGAAUUUCACCUCAAUAAUCUAAAAGUCAGAAAUGCUGGAGAGUACACCUGUGAAUACUACAGAAAAGCAUCCCCCCACAUCCUUUCACAGCGCAGUGACGUCCUUCUACUGUUGGUGACAGGACAUUUAUCUAAACCUUUCCUCCGAACCUACCAAAGGGGUACAGUGACCGCAGGUGGAAGGGUGACUCUGCAGUGCCAGAAGCGAGACCAAUUGUUUGUGCCUAUCAUGUUCGCUCUACUGAAGGCAGGGACGCCAUCACCCAUCCAGCUGCAGAGUCCAGCGGGGAAGGAGAUAGACUUCUCUCUGGUGGACGUGACAGCCGGCGAUGCUGGGAACUACAGCUGCAUGUACUACCAGACAAAGUCUCCCUUCUGGGCCUCAGAACCCAGUGAUCAGCUUGAGAUAUUGGUGACAGUUCCCCCAGGUACCACAUCGAGCAACUACUCCCUGGGUAACUUCGUACGACUGGGUCUGGCUGCCGUAAUUGUGGUUAUCAUGGGAGCUUUCCUGGUGGAGGCCUGGUACAGCCGGAAUGUGUCUCCAGGUGAAUCAGAGGCCUUCAAACCAGAGUGACUCCAUCUUGAACCGGGGCUGGGUAAACUGAGGCUGCAACCUGCUGGACUGCAUUCCCAGGGGGUUGAGGCUUUCUAAGUCACAGGAUGAGACAGGUCACAACAUACA